GAGAUAGAGUCCCACUCUUCUGCCCAGUCUGGAGUGCAGUGGUGUGAUCUUGGCUCACUGCAACCUCUGCCUCCUGGGUUCAAACAAUUCUCAUGCCUCAGCCUCCCGAGUAGGUGGGGAUUACAGGCAUGUGCCACCACACCCAGCUAACUUUUUGUAUUUUAGUAGAGAUGGGGUUUCACUGUGUUGACUGGGCUGGUCUUGAAUUCCUGACCUCAAGUGAUCCUCCCACCUUGGCCUCCCAAAUGUAUCUUUUGAUGAAACUGAGAUAAGGAAAAUACAUUUUAUAGUUUUUGUACUAACCUUACUUGUCUAUUCAUUUACCAUUUGAUAUCAUUUCCUUACUUUCAGUAAAGUUUGUCACUACUGACCCCUUUGUCCAUUCGUGCAUUCAUUCAUUCAUUCCUUCAUUCAGUCAUUCAUUUAUUGAGAGACGGAGUCUCGAUUUGUCGCGCAGGCUGGAGUAGUGGCAUGAUCUUGGCUCAAUGCAACUUCUGUCUCUGAGUUCAAGUGAUUCUGGGUUCAAGCGAAUCCCUCCGGAGUAGCUGGGAUUACAGGUGUGAGCCACCAUGCUCAGCCCUGAUUUCUGAUUUGACUCCAUUCUAGUAAGAUUUAAAUCCCUAAGACUUAAGUUCUUGGAAAUUUGAGACUUGCUUUAUGGUUCAACAUAUGGUCUUUUUGGGUAAACAUUCCUUGUGUACAACAACAAAAUAUUUAUAGACUACAGUUGUUAGAUGUGGUGUAAUAUGUUCUAUCAAGUUUGUUUCUGUUUCAGAUUUUUACUGCUUUUGCAUUUGUUUGCUCCUAUUCAGACAAAGGUUUGUUAAAAUAUCCCCAAAUGAUUAUAACAUUUGUCUCUCUGUUUAAUUUGUCAGUUUUUGUUUUAUAUAUUUUGAUUAUGUUAAAGUGCUGACAAGUCAAGGUUUUUUUAAAUCUACCUGGUGAAUCAAACUUUUUAUUAUUGUGACGUGUCCCUCUUUAUCUCAGUAUUGCAUUUUACCUUGUAGUGUUUUUAAUCUAGUGUUAAGGCAGAUACACUAACUUUCAUUUGGUGUUUGCAUGCUACAGCUUUUUCCAUUCUUUCAGCUUUCGCGUUUUAGCCAUAUCUUUUAAGUUGCAUAUACUAGUUUAAAUAAACUAGUUUGACCAUGUUUGUUCUUUAAUUGGAACAUGUAGUACAUUUACAUUUAAUAUACUUGCUGAUAUGUUUAAAUUGAUAUUCCUAAUAAAUGAUUUCUGUUUAUCCUGUUUGAACUUUCUCUUAUUCUCCUUUUCUGCUGCUUUUGGGAUUAUUAUUAUUUUUUGUUCCAAAUACCCCCCACCCCCCAACUUGGCUUAAUAGUUAGACCAUCUUUUUUUAAAUUUGUUUUUAAUAUUUAUCCUAGAGAUUACAAUAUGCCUCCUUUCUGUGUUAAAGUGUGAUAUAAGUUAGCACUUUUUUCUCUUUCUGGUCAGUGCAGCAACAUUAGAAAACAUUAACUGUACAUUUCCCUCUCCAGAAUUACAUACUAUUGCCAGAUAGUUUAGUUCUCUGAUAUUUUAACUCCCCACAAGAUAUUACCAUUAGUGUUUUAUUCAGUAAUUAUACAUUUAAAUUUGUUUAUAUACUCAGUUUUUUUCUUCAAUCUUUAGUGCAUUUCCAGGCUUCUAGCUGGGUUGAUUUUCUCUCUGAAAAUACUCUUUUUUUUCUCUAUUUGGGCCUAUCUGUUGAGGAAUUCUUUUUUGCUUAUCUGAUAAUGCUUUUUUUUCAUUUUUAUUCUUGAAGGGAUUUUUUUGGGGGGAGGGAGCUGGAUACAGAAAUCUUGGUUGGCAGUUUUUUUCAUUUGUCAUGUUGCAGCUAUGCACAGUGCCCUUGAGACCUGGUUUCCAGAGUUUCUGUUGAGAAGUCAACUAUCAGUCUUACUGUUGCUCCUUUGACUGUAAUCUAGCUUGUAGAUCUCUGGUCACUUUUUGUUUUUGUUGGAGUGGGGGUGUUUAUAUUUGGUUUUCAGCAGUUUUACUGUGAUAUGUCUAGGUGUGAUCUUUUAUUUGUUCAGCUUGGUGUUUAUAGGACUUCUUAUAACUGUGACGUAGGACUGCACUGCCCAGUGCCAGCCACUAGCUGCAUGUAACUGUUGAUACCAAUUAACAUUUAAAAAGUUAAAAAUUCAAUUCCUCACAUUUUAAGUUCUCAGUAGACAAAUGUUUCUAUUAGUUACUCUAUUGGCAGAUGGAGAACAUUUCCAUCAUUCUAUCAAUAGAAUAGAAAGUUCUGUUGCACAGGACUGAUGAGCUCGUUCGUCAGUUUUGGAAAAUUCUCAGACUAUAUCACUUCGGAUAGUGCUUCUGUCUUGUCAUCUUCUUUCCUCCUGGUACUCCAGUUAUACAUGUAUUAAACAUUCUUAAAUUUGCCCUAUGUUUCUUACAUCCUUUUUUGUAUGUUUUAUCUUUUUAUUCCUGUGUGCAUUUUUAAAGAUAUAUUUUUCUGACCAAUCUUCCAUUUCAUUAAUUCUCUUAGGCUGUGUCUAAUAUGCCAUCAGACUCAUACACUGAGUUCUUUAAUUUAGUUUAUUUUACUUUUUGGUUCUAGAAUUUCAAUUUUAUUCUCUUUAGUUUCAGGUUUUCUGCUAAAGUUCUCAGUGUUAACUACUCAGCAUACUUAUUCGAGAGUCUGUGUCUGAUAACUUAAUUAUCUAGAUACCUUUGGGUCUUGUUCCAUGUUUCAUUUGCAUUUUAUUUGCGUUAUUUUCUUGGAUUUCUGGUUAAUUUUUAUUGUGUAUGAGACAUUUGAUGUGAAAAACUGUAGAAAUAAUUUGAGGCCUAGAAUAAUGGUAGUCUUCCAUGACAUAAAAUUUACAUUUAAUUUUGACAGAAACAUAGGGGCCCUAUAAAUCUGCUUUUCUUAAUUCACUUUUAAGGAUUGAGAUUAUUUGAAUCUGGGCUUUAAUUGUAAUUCUUUUGCUCUGAGGUUGAGAUCCCAACCCAGAGUUUGGGGGAGGCUCAGGGUCUCAUUUUUGUCUGGCUAACCCAGUGAGGCUUUCAGAUGUUUUGCUUAGCUUUCCAGCCUCACAGUCACUACUUAAAUCAGCAGAUGCCUGUAGGGGAGAAGAAACCUGGUAUACCAGACUCACUUCUGGGAACUUAGUGAAUUCUGGCCCCAUUUCUUUACUGCCUGAUCUCUAGAAGUAGAGUUUUCGUUUUUUAAACUUAGUUCAACUUUUCAAGUUUCUUCAGCCAGAAGAUUGGUUUGAUGACCUGAUCACCAUUACUGGAAGGAGAAAGUCCUUGUUUGCUUUUAUUUUUAAUUCUUUAAUUGGCUUUGAAAUUUUGGGUGAAUCUGAAUCUUUUUCUCCUCUUAACCACGCUCUUCUUCUCUCACUCUCUUUAUCUUCCUUUUGUUUAAAUUAUCAAUUGGUUAUAUCGGGUCCACAACACCAGGGCUGCAUACCUGUACUGGUCGCUAUCCUGUGAGGAAUGAGCCACACAGCGGGAGGUGAGCAGCAGGCCAGUGAGCAUUCCCGCCUGAGCUCCACCUCCUGUGAGAUCAUCCGUGGCAUUAGAUUCUCAGAGGAGCGUGGACCCUGUUGUGAACUGCACAUGCGAGGGAUCUAGGUCGCUUGCUCCUUAUGAGAAUCUAACUAAUGCCUGAUGAUUUGAGGUGUAACAGUUUCAUCUGAAACCAUCUCCACUCCACCCCACCCCACCCCACCCCACCCCUGGUCCAUGGAAAAAUUGUCUUCCAUGAAACUGGCCACUGGUGCCAAAAAGGUUGGGGACCACUGGGUUAUAUACAGAGUUUGAAUAGGACCAACUUGUGGAGCAGUUAGCCAUCUGGAAUUGUAGGUUUAAUUGGAAGCAGAACUAUUUUUGCCUUUGAUGCCUUGAAGAUAACCGGUUUUUGUUGUUGUUGUUGUUGUUUGUUUGUUUGUUUUUGAGACAGAGUCUCACUCUGUUGCCCAGGCUGGAGUGCAGUGGUGGGAUCUCGGUUCACUGCAACCUCUGCCUCCCAGAUUCAAGCGAUUCUCCUGCCUCAGCCUCCCGAGUUAGCUGGGACUCGUGUGCCACCAUGCCCAGCUAAUUUUUGAAUCUUUAGUAAAGACAGGGUUUCGCCUUGUCGUCCAGGCUGGUCUCAAACCCCUGACCUCUGGAGAUCUGCCCGCCCCUGCCUCCCAAAGUGCUGGGAUUACAGGCGUGAGCCACCAUGCCCAGCCAGAUUACUGUUAUUUUAAGUUUUUUUGGCAACCGGCUAGUACCAAUGUAAGUUAAGUUUGGAUUCAAAUAAAAUCGUCAGAGCAUUACAAUAUAUUUUUAAAAGACAGCUCUUCGUGAAAUAACAUUAUAUAUAAUAUGUGUGUGUAUAUAUAUAUCCUAUUCCUUUAAUGCUGGGUAUUUUCUCAGCUCUGUACUCAAUUCUUUGUCCUGUAAGUAAAAAUGUGAUACACGUCUUAGUCACUUUGCUUCUUUUAAAUUAUAACCCUUUGAGCAGUAGUUUAAUAUAAAAAAGUUUUAGCUUUCGAAACAGACUUUUAGAGUUGCUCAUACUGUAUAACACCCUUUAUGCCUUUGGAAAAUUUCAUCUUAUGUAUUGUAGUUACUGUUUCAAUUUAUUGAUUAUUUAGUAAAAAAAUAUGAAUGUCUUUGUGGAUGUUACUGUAUUGUACGAGUUGUAACUUUAGAGUGCCACUAGCAACAUACAUAUGAACCAGUUUAAUGGAAACAUUACUGCUCUUAGUAUUUUUAGGAAGUGUUUGGCUUGUUAAGUAGGGGUGGUAUUACAUGUUAUUUUACUUACUACAUAUAUUUGAUUACCAAGAGAUUAAGCAGUUUUCCACGUGUUUAUUACUGUUUCUAUUUGUGACUUGUUUUAAAAAUUAAAACAGUCUUAAAUCUCAUCUUGGACUUGUUACUCCUGCUCAUUACUGCCAAGGCUUACUAUAGUAUUUACAAACUACAAGGAGUGUGAUAGUUUUUAUGUUAAGAUUACUUAAAUUUCUUUGGACUAAUUUUCUUCUCUAGCUUGAGAAAAAAAUGAUUGGGAUUUUUAAGAGGGAUUACGUUAUUUCGUACUGUCCUCCAAAUGCUGCCAUCUGAAAUUUGAAGGUUUGCAGUAUUUUUUAGAUAAGUAUACCUUGGUAUGGGAGCCUCUGUGCUAGGACCAAUUUAUAGUAGUUCUCUACUCUCUAUUUGCUAUUAUAAAGCCAAAAUAAAUAUAUUAAAUAUGUCGUUGUAAGUAUAUUAGUAUUUAGCAAAUUCUCUUCUUCCUUAAAUUUUAUGUUAAUAAGUUAACUGGCUAAAACAAAUGUGUACAUGGCCAGUUAGAACACUGUCUAAAACUUCUUGAUAUAAGCAAACAUUUUAGUUAUCUUUGAAAGCUCACACGAUAAAUUACAACCCCUAUCUCUACCCCCUUGAGCUUGCUUUUAAGAAAGUGAUAAAAGUGAUGCAAACUUUUUAUCAUUAGUUCUCAAUAAUUUUAUUGUAUAAUUUAACUUUUAUAGGAUGCCUUUUCUAAAUUUGUAUGAAGUAAAAAUAACUUUCAGUCCAGUUAUUUGAGAAGACAAAGCUGUAUAACUGAAUAGUUGUAUAAAUCCUGUUUAUUAAGAGUGCUCAAAGAGCUUAAUAACUAAUGAAAGUUUUUUUUUUAUUUUUUACUUUUUUAUUUUAUUUUAUUUUUUUUUGAGACAGAGUCUCACUCUGUCACCCAGGCUGUAGUGCAGUGGCGCGAUCUCAGCUCACUGCAACCUUCACCUCCUGGGUUCAAGCAUUUCUCCUGCCUCAGCCUCCCGAGUAGCUGGGACUACAGGCACACGCUGCCACACCCGGCUAAUUUUUUGUAUUUUAGUAGAGACGGGGUUUCACCAUGUUGCCCAGGUUGGUCGCGAACUCCUGAGCUCAGGCAAUCCGCCCACGUUAGCCUCCCAAAGUGUUAGGAUUACAGACGUGAGCCACUGCGCCUGGCUGAAAGUUUAUCUUAAAACUGAGGCUUAUUCCGGAUACUAAAGAUAUUAAACAAGGCAUAUGUGCAUGUGCCUGGGUGUAUAUGUAGAUGGCUUGGGGGUAGAAAUAAAAUAAAAAGCCACAGAAAAGGCUAUGGCUUUUUAUUUUUUAAAAAAUCACUUCAUUGAAUCAACAUUUUAAUUUGUUGAUAUUCUUUUUUGAAUUUACUUCGUUUUAUUUCUGCUCUGCAUCUAAUUCCUUAUUUGGGAUAAGAUAUAGAGCAUGAGUCAGCAAACUUUUUUUUUUUUGAAACAGGGUCUCACUCUGUCACCCAGCCUGGAGUACAGUGGCAUGAUCUCAGCUCAUUGCAGCCUUGACCUCCAAGCCUCAAGCAGUCCUCUCACCUUGCCUGGCUAAUUUUUAUAUUUUUUGUAGAGAUGGGUUUCACCAUGUUACUCAGACUGUUUUUGAAUUCCUGAGCUCAAGCAAUCCACCAGUCUUGGCUUCCCAAAGUGCUGGGAUUACAAGUGUGAGCCACCACACCUGGCCUAAACUGUUUUAAAAGAGUUGUCACAACUACGACAGGUGCUUGUGUUUGUGUGGUAAAGUGCAGCCAUAGACAAUAUGCUAACAAGUGGGAUGACUGUGUUCUUUAAAACCUUACUAUGGACACUGAUAUUUGAAUUUCAUAUUGAUUUUACUAAUCACAAAGUAGUCUUGAUUUUUUUACCUUAUAAUAUUUAACAGGGUAGUCACUGCUGCCCGUCCUUGUAUAGAGUAACUUUCCUUGAGGAAGUUCAACCCUUCUAGUUACCCAGCUAUCCAGGUAGUUGAAAGUUUUAAGUUAAAGAGCAGAUGUUUCUCUGACUUUUCAUAGAUCAAGAAAAGUCAAGGACCAAAAUUGUUAGCUCUGUACAUAUGCAAACAUUUUAGCCAUUUUUUUUCAAAAUUGUAAUUGUGGUUAAAAAACACACGACAUAAAAUGUACCAUCUUAGCCUUUUCUUUUCCUUUCCUGUCCUGUCUUGUCCUGUCCUUUUUUGAGACAGCGUCUCACUCUGUCACCCAGGCUGGAGUGCAGUGGUGCAACCUCCGCCUCCCAGGUUCACUUGCCUCAGCCUCUGGAGGCUGCCACCCUGCCUGGCUACCUCUUAGCCAUUUCUAAGUCGGUAGUGUUAAGUGUAUUCCUGUUGUUGUGCAGCUAAUCUCCAGAAUGUUUUCGUUUUGUCAAACUGUAACUUUACACCCAUUAAACAACUUUCUAAUUCCCCUCUGCCCCUAGGCCCCAGCAACCACUAUUCUACUUUCUGUCUCUGUAAGUUUCACUACUCUAGAUACCUCACAGAACUGGAAUCAUAUAGUAUUUGUCAUUUUGUGUCUGACUUAUUUCCCUCAACAUAACGUCUUCAAGGUUCACCCAUAUUGUGUCAUGUUUCAGUGUUUCCUUCCUUUUUAAGGCUGAAUAAUAUUCCAUAGUACGUGUGUACCACAUUUUGUUUAUCCAUUCAUCUUUUGAUUGGACAUGGGUUGCUUCCACUUCUUGGGUAUCGUGAGUAGUGCUGCUAUGAACAUGGGUGUGCAGCAAUGUCUUUGAGAUCCUGCUUUCUAUUUUCUAUCUAGCUGUACCAUUUUACAUUCCUACUGACAGUACACAAAGGUUCCCAUUUUUCCACAAUCCUUGACAACACUUUUUUUCAGUGUUUUUGAUGGUAGCCAUUCUAAUAGGUGUGAGGUGAUAUCUUAUUGUAUUUUUUUAUUUACAUUUUGCUAAUAAUUAGUGGUGUUGAGCAUCUUUUUCUUUUUUUCUUGUCGCCCACGUUGGAGUGCAGUGGUGCGACCUCAGCUCACUGCAGCCUCUGCCUCCCGGGUUCAAGCGAUUCUCCUGCCCCAACCUCUGGAGUAGCUGGGAUUACAGGUGCCCACCACCACUCCCGGCUAAUUUUUUACAUUUUUAGUAGAGAUGGGGUUUUACCAUGUUGGCCAGGAUGGUCUCGAACUCCUGACCUCAGGUGAUCCACCCUCCUCGGCCUCCCAAAGUGCUGGGAUUAUAGGCAUGAACCACCGUGCCUGGCCAUCUUUUUCUUUUUUAAGAGAUAGGAUCUUGUUACAUUGCCCAGGCUGGCCCCAAACUCCUGAGCUCAAAUGAUCCUCCCACCUCAGCCUCCAGACACUAUGCCUAGCUCAAUUAAUAUUUUUAAUUGGCAAAUCAUAAUUGUAUACAUUUAUGGGGUACAGUGUCAUGUUUUGAUAUAUAUAUAUAUAUAUAUAUAUACACACACACACACACAAACACACACAUAAUGUGGAAUGAUUAAACAAAGCUAAUUAACAUAUCGGUCACCUCCUUUAAUUUUUCCAGCAAGACAUUUGAAAUUUAUUCUUUUAGCUAUUUUGAAAUACAUGUCAUAUAUCAUUAUUAACUAUAGUCACCCUGCUGUGCGAUGGAUCUCAAAAACUUAUUUUUUCUGUCUAACUCAAACUUUGUGUCCUUUGACCAACAUUUCCUCAUUUCUCCCAGCCCCUGGUAACCACUAUUCUUUCUGCUUUUGUGUGUUCAAAUUUUUUAGAUUCCACAUGUAAGUGAGAUUAUGUGGUAUUUGUCUUUCUGUGCCUGGCUUAUUUUACUUUGUCCUCUAAGUUCAUCCAUGUUGUUUCAAAUGACAGGAUUUCCUUCUUUUUUAAGGCUGAAUAGGUCCGGCUCAGUGGCACAUGCCUGUAAUCCUAGCACUUUGGGAGGCUUAGGUGGAAGGAUUGCUUGAGCUCCACCUCAAGCACCCCUUGAGGUGUGAGCUGUGAUGGCACUACUGCUCGCCAGCUUGGGCGACAGAGCAAGACCCUGUCUCAAAAAAAAAAAAAAAAAAAAAAAGGCCAAAUAGUAUUACAUUGUAUAUAUACCACAUUUUUUUUUUUUUCCUAUUCAUCUGUUGAUGGACAUUUAGGUUGAUUCUGUAUCUUGGCUAUUGUGAAUAGUGCUGCAGUGAACAUGGGAGUGCAGAUAUCUCCUUAACAUAAUGAUUUCAGUUUCUUUGGAUAUAUAGAAAUGGGAUUGCUGGAUGUGAGCAUCUUUUCAUUUCUUGGCCAUUUAUAUAUCAUCUCUGGAGAAAUGUCUGUUCAGAUUCUUUGCCCAAUCGUUAGUCAAGUUGUUAGCCAACUAUAUUUUAAUAAUACUUUCUUUUCUCUCUUGCAGUGUGUCACAAGUACAAUUAAAUAAGAAAUUAACAUAAUUUAAUCCUUACUUACAAAGGUAAUAUAUUGCAAGAAUGAGGAGAACAGUAAGGGGAAUUUCUGAUUUGCUAAAUGCCAGUCUAAUAGAGAAGCUGACCAUUCCAUAAUUGUUUUUAAAGUACAUGAACAGCAAUCUGAGAGGAUGAAAUAUAUAUAUAAUGUGACUAAAAAAGAUAUGGGAUUGAUUUUUAUGUGUCAUAUAGAAUUAAUCAUACCUUGCCUAUAUAUUAUAAUCAAAUUGUCUGUUAAGCAGAUAAAUUUAGAGAACUGUUAUGCUGCAUGGCAUUUAGGUUUACAUGCUGAGGAAGAAAAAAACUUGAAAUGAUUGUGGCUGGGCACAUAACAAUGAAUUUUAUGGAUUAAAAAAAACAGCCAGGUAUGGUGGCACAUCUCUGUAGUCCUCAGCUACUUGGGAGAAGGUGGGAGGAUUGCUUGAGCCGGAGAGUGAGGCUGCAGUUAGCUGCGAUCAUGCCACUGCACUCCAGCCUGGGCAACACCCUGACACCAUCACAAUGUAUAUGAAACAUAAAUAAAUGUUAUGUUUAGACUUGGGUCCCAUCCCCCAGAUACCUCAUUAUGUACACUCAAAUAUUAAAAAAAAAAAAAAAUCAGAAGUCUGAAACAUGUUGCUCCUGGGCAUUUUGGAUAAGGGAUACUCAACCUGUAUUCAUCAUUGUUCAUAGUUAGACACUAUGAACUAUCAGUGUCUAAAGCCAGAAAGAAACCAUUCCCUUUUCUUUUUUUAAAAAAGCUUAUUUUAUAUUAUUUUAGACAGGGUCUCACUCUGUCUCCCAGGCUGAAGUGCCUUGGUAGAGUUUCAGCUCACUGCAACCUCUGCCUCCUGGAUUCAGGUGGUUCUCGUGCCUCAGCCUUGCGAAUAGCUGGGAUUACAGGCACCUGCCACCAAGCCCGGCUAAUAUUUUUGUAUUUUUAGUAGAGACAGGGUUUCCCCAUGUUGGCCAGGCUGGUCUGGAACUCCUGACCUCAAGUGAUCCACCCUCCUCAGCCUUCCAAAGUGCUGGGAUUACAGACAUGAGCCUGCGCCUGAAUUCAGUCUGUCACCAAAUCUUGUUGUUUUUUCUCUCUUAGAUACUUUUCUUAUCUGUCACUGUUCUAGUUAGGCUCCUAUUUUCUCUUAACCUGGAUGGCUGCCUAACAUGUCCCCAUGUUUCCCCUCUGGAAUCUACUGUUAGGCAAAAAGGCAGAAGCUAUAGUACUUGACAGGUAACAAUGUUUAAUUUUCAACUUGACUAAAGUAGCUCAGCUUGUGUCCCUUUUAUUUUUAUUAUUAUAUAGUUUUACAUAUUGAGCUCCAAGAAGUUAUAGUUCCUUGGUUUUUAAAUAAGAUCUGUAAGAGGAGUUUAAUCCAUAUUUAGUGUUGUGUUAAUCUUCAAGCCAGUAAGUUAGACAUUUAUUCUCAUUUUACAAAUAAAGAAAUCGUUGCUGAGAGUUAACUGUGUGGUGGAGUUGAGAUUUAGAUUUAGUGUUUUGUUAUGUUUUUUGAGACAGUGUCUCACUUUGUUCCCUAGGCUGGAAUGCAGUGGCGUGUUCAUAGCUCACUGCAGCCUUGAUCUCUGGGGUCAAGGGAUUCUCCCACCUCAAUCUCUUGAGUAGUUGGGAUCACCCCACCCAGCUAAUUUUUUGAUGUUUUGUUGAGAUGAGGUCUUACUAUGUGGCCCAAGCUGAUCUUGAACUCGGAAGCCAUAGCACCUGGCUAACAGCCAUCAGUAUUAAACACAAAAGUGUAAGUGUCCCUUUUAGGCUUUUAAUUAUCUUAGAAAACAGCUAUUUGUAAAGAAACUUAAAAAACUUUUACUAAAAUACCACUACGCUGUAUUAUUAGAGUACUAACAUUAAUAUGCAGUGAACUUAUACAAAUACGUAAGUUUAUAAUUUAUCUGAAACUCGUGUUGGGGGGGGUAAGUAACUUUAUGAGUUUCUGGAUAUAUGACUACUGUUGAUAUGGUUUAGCUGUGUCGCCAUCCAAAUCUCAUCUUGAAUUGUAGUUCCCAUAAUCUCCAUGUGUCCUGGAAGGGACUCGGUGGGAAGUGACUGGAUCAUGGGGGCGCUUUCCCACAUGCUGGGUCUCCUCCCGAUAGUGAGUUCUCACAAGAUGUAAUGGUUUUGUAAGUGUUUGGCAUUUCUCCUGCUUGCACUCAUUCUUCUGCUGCUCUGUGAAGAGGUGCCUUUGGCCAUGAUUGUAAGUUUCCUGAGGCUUCCUCAGCCAUGAAGAACUGUGAGUCAAUUAAACCUCUUUUCUUUAUAAUUACCCAGUCUCAGGUAUUUCUUCAUAGCAGUGUGAGAACGGACGAAUACAAUGGUAAAGAAAAACAAACCCAAACUGAGAAUUGGAUGGAUGGAGAUUUUAUGUAAGAUCUUUCAUUUAGCAGUACGUCAGCUAGUGAUAAAUAUAUCAUGUGAUGAACUUUCAGGAUUUUGUACACAUUUUCAUAAUUGUAAAUGUAAAAGUGUCUUUGAAUGCCAGGGGCUACCACUGUAUAAAAUGUAAUCUCAAUUGUUGGAAAAAAAAAAAGUAUGUGGAAAAAAAGACUGGAAGAAAAUAAGCCAUUGUUGACAUUGGUUAUCUUUGGGUGGUAGGACUAUGAGUGGGAUUUUUUUGGCUUUAAUUUUUUGCAUUUUUCCAUUUUUCUUUACCAUGCGUUCAUGAUUACGGGUAAAAAGGGAAAGAAGUGAAAUUGCUUCUUUCCUGACAGUUUUUUAGGAAAAUAUCCUUUUGUUCAUAAGGCAAAUAAAUUGUCUUGGGGAAGAAAUAUGAAGAAAUAUGAAGUCAGAAAUAUAAUAAUUGAAAGAAGUCUUGGUAUAAGUCAGUAUUUUUAAGUGACUGUUUGCUGGAAAACUAUGGUGUUAAUCUGAGGCCAACCAGGCAUAUGACUAUAGAACUUUGCAUCUGCCACUCUGUUUUGGCAGCUUUUAGAGUUAUACAAAAAAGGUACGAGAAUGAUGUGACCCACAAUUUAUUUGAAUCACUAAAUACUGUCCAAAAAUGGCAGUUACAGUAAUUUGUGAGGACACUAGGGGAUCUGAUUAUAUCAUAGGCCAUUUUGGUCAUUGAGUAUUAGGUUGAACCAUAUGAACCUAUUUUAUAGAUUAAAAAUGGUUGAGUGUCUGUAACUUCCUGUGAUUUAACCUGUUAAAAAUAGUACUUUUUCAUCCUUCAUUCAAAUUUGAUUUACAUAGCUUGUAUUAUAUACAUAUUUCUGUAUCUAUCUAUAUAUCUCUGUAUCUCUCUCUAUAUAUAGAUAUAUAGAUCUCUGCAUCUAUCUAUAUAUAUAGAUACAAAGAUAUAUAGGUAUCUAUCUAAGUUUACAGGUUGGUGUGUCCGUUAAGGUUGCAGAUAAAAGAAAUUAUUAUUAGAAUCUUAAAAUUUUGAUUUUGGGGUGAUUUGGUCUUUGGAAAUAUGUCUUUCUAGAGGACCAUUAUGACCUUAAUGUGGAUUAUGUGCUAAUUUAUAUAUCUGGAUCCCAAAGUUGGCAUUCCCUGGAGUCUUGAUAGCACGUUAGAGUUGGAAGUGAUGGUUAAAGAUUGUUUUAGUUUUCAUCAAGCAGGAUAACUCAACAUGUCUACGUGGACAUGUAGAGCAGGUAGGAGCCCUAUCCUACGUAGGCUAGCCUGUUUUAUUGGAAAUCUGGUGGAUAAAAUUUAUUUAUUUUUGUUCCUUAUUUGAAGGUUUAGGCUAGGUGAGUAGAAAGUGAGUAGAUUGGAAUGCUAAUAUGUUCCUUCUGUUGCUUUCUCUUCUCACGUGAUUUACUUUGCAUGUAUUUUUGGGCAAGUUGCUUAUUUUUCUGGGACUUAGUAAGUAAACAUCAUUUAGGCUAAUAUGGUCCAGGAACCUGCCAAAACCUUACAUGUAUUAUCUCAUUUAACUCACCUUAUGAAUUAACGCUGUGUCCUGCCUGUGAACAACCCUGUGAUGGACAUAGUCAUUACCAAGAUUUUUUUUUUCCCCGAGAUAGAGUUGCUCUGUUGCCCAGGCUAGAGUGCAGUGGUGCGAUCUUGGCUUACUGCAGCCUCCGCCUCCUGGGUUCAAGCAAUUCUCCUGCUUCAGCCUCCUGAGUAGCUGAGACUACAGGCACAUGCCACCACGCCCAGCUAAUUUUUGUAUUUCUAGUAGAGAGGGGGUUUCACCAUGUUGGCCAGGUUGGUCUUGAACCCCUGACCUUGUGAUCUGCCCGCCUCAGCCUCCCAAAGUGCUGGGAUUAUAGGCAUGAUCCACUGUACCCAGCCGUUAUUACCAAGAUUUUAUAAUAAUCGGGUCACUACGUGGCAAAGCUGGGAUUUGAACUCAGGCAGUCUGGCCACAGAGCCCAUGUUCUUAACCUUACAGCUGGCUGUAUUGUUAAAAUAAAUGUCCACAGAAAUCAAUUUUAGGAAUCUUACGAGGAUAUGGUAAAGAUGAUGUUGAUGAAAUAAUAGGUUGAAAUCACUGUAUGAAUAUUUAGAAUAUUUAGAAUUUUACCCAUGUUAUGUUAUGUUAUGUUAUGUUAUGUUAUGUUAUGUUAUGUUAUGUUAUGUUAUUUGGUAACCUAUCUAUAUCCCAGGCUGGAGUGCGGUGGCAGCAUUUCACAGCUUACUACCACAGCCUCUACUUCCUGGGCUCAAGUGAUCUUCCCACCUCAGCCUGGGACUAUAGGUGCGGACUACCAUGCCUGGAUAAUUUUUUAAAUUUUUUUGUAGAGAUGGGGUCUCUUCAGGUUGCCCAGGCUGGUCUCGAACUCCUGGGCACAAAGGACCUGCCUGCCUUGGCCUUCAAAGUGCUGGGAUUACAGAUGUGAGACACCACUCCUGGCCCCUUGUUGAUUUUCAUUCAUUGUUUUCAGUUGUGCUUUAAUAGGUAGAUCGUAUUCAACUUGGACUUCUUACAAAAAGUACUUGCAGCCUCCUUUUUGGUCAGGGAUCUACUUACCUGCUGUAAAGGGACUUUAAGAAAGAAAAACUGUUCUGUGGCCCUUCUUUCACCCUGUAUUAUUGGGAUAGAAGAAUAGGCCAAGAAGGAGUACUGUGGAGCAGUAAAUCAUCACUGUCCUUUUUAAGGUUCAUAACAAUUGGUUACCUCUCAGGAGUGGGAUUUGGAGACAAGGAGGUAUUGGGACUUUUUACUUUUAUAUUUUUGUAUUUAUUUCAAGAAGCACCUAUUACUUAGUAAUGAGGGAAAGGGAUGAAACCAAAAAAGAGUCUUGAGUACUUAGGUUAGAGACAAGAUACCAGUCUACUUUCUGGUAGUGAGGAGAGGGUAAUUACCAGCUCAAGUUUUACCAGAUUCCUGUUUUGGAGUUUUCUUAGAGAACAUUCCUUCUUACUGCAGGAUCAAGUACAUGCUCUGUUUUUCUCUGUGUCUCUGACACGGACACGUGCACACACACAUACACACACACACACACAUACUCUUCCUCUGGACCCUUCUUUUGGGACAGAGAUGCUUAGUUGAGUGGAUAUAAACUAUAACAAAAGGCAGUAUAACUUAACCUUUCAGUGUCUCAAUUUCUUUAUUUUUAAAAUCAGGACUAUAUGUUAAUACAGAAAUGCAGUCUAGUAUAAAAUACAUCUAUAUGUGAGUAUGUGUAUAUACAUUUGUAUGUAUGUGUAUAUAUAUAUACAUGUACAUGUAUAUACACAAUGUGAGAGAUUGAUUUUAAAAAUAGCAGAUUGUCACAAGUUUGAGGCUAGAGGAAGAGGAACUUGGUUAGUUGUGUUACUACUAUAUUAGCAUAAAGAAAUUAGGCACGGAAGUAUAUGUAAUCCUAUUAUACUUAGCAGGAACUUCUAACCCCAGGAAGAAAGCUAGAAGGGGGCUUAUUACAUUAUAUAUGCUAAUAUUUAUUGAGCACUUAUAUUUUAGCAUACAUAUAUGUUCACAUUUAUUGAAUGCUUUCUAAGUGACAGAUUUAGUUCAAAACUAUUCAUAGAAACUUAUUUUACUUUAACAACUCUAUAAGGUAUGUACUUUUAUUAUCUCCAUUUUCUAUAUAAGGAAGCUAAAAUAGAGAGAGAUUAAAGAACUUGACCAAACUUUACACAACUUAUCGACCUACGUAUGUUUUUGAUGAAAGAAAAAUUAGUUGUCAGAUUUUUUUAUUAGUAAGAAUAAAAUUGAAAUUUAAAUUAUUUUCAUUUUUUAAGGUCAUGGCAGUAGAGAGAAGCAGAAACCCUAUGCUUUAGUAACUCUGAUGCAAGCCAUAUCUCCUUAUAUGAAUUAUUUGGUCUCAGAGUAUUUGAAUUCUUUGCUGUAAGGGUUGCAACAAAAGUGUUUAAAAAGACCAAUUAUAUUAAAAAGAUUAGGUGAAGCAUUACUCUGACUUGGAAUGAUUCUAGAUUAGACCUGUCUUCUCUACCACAGGGUUAUAUAAUUGAACAUGUAUACCUAGAUUCAGGGACCUGACUUUCUAUACUUACUGUUGUCAGACAUUUGGGUGAAAUCUUCGGAAAGUGUGUGUCUGUGUUUAUGUGUGUAUGUGCAGUACAUAUAUAUCUAUAUAUGUAGAUAGAUGGAUAGAUAAUAUGACUCAGAAACAGAUAAAUAGUUUAGUGAAACUAUUUAGUGAAUAAAGUACAAAACAGACCGAUGUUUAUGGAAUGUGAUAACCAGAGAGGUAUUUUAAAUUAGUGGGAAAAGUUUGAAUUGGUGAGAAAUUGGGACAUUUUCCUUUGGAAAAAAAUUAGAUAUAUAUCUAUAUAUAAUUCUAAAUGGAUUAAUGUUCUAAAUGUUAAUAUUUGAAAUCAUUAGAAAAAAAUGUAGGAAAUGGGUUUAUUGAAUUCAUGUGAGGGAAGGGUUAGAAAAAGAAAUUGGGCUGGUUUUGUGAUAGCUCAUUUAACUAACAUGUUCAUUUAACUGCCAAAAAAUUAGAAUAUUUGGUUUUAAAGUAGGGAAUCAAACUGUGGAAUAAAUAAUGCAACAUAGUAUAGCCAACAAAAGUUAUAGCUAAAUAUGGUACAAAAUAUUGUCAAUGAAAAUAGGUAUGUUCUAUUUAUUAACCAUGUUAAAAUGGAUGUUUCAAGACAAGAUUCAGAAGUAAUUCCAGUGUUAUACAAUAUAGACUUCUUGAAUUUUUUCUUUCUUUUUUUUUUUUUUUUGAGACGGGAGUCUCACUCUGUUGGCCAGGCUGGAGUGCAGUGACAUGAUCUCAGCUCACUGCAACCUCCGCCUCCCGGGUUCAAGUGAUUCUCGUGCCUCAGCCUCCUGAGUCGCUGGGAUCACAGGUGUGCACCACCACGCCUGGCUAAUUUUUGUAUUUUUUAGUAGAAUUGGGGUUUCACCAUGUUUACCAGGCUGGUCUUGAUCUCCUGACCUCAGGUGAUCCACUCACCUCAGCCUCCCAAAGUGCUGGGAUUACAGGCGUGAGCCACCGUGCCCAGCCCAGACUUUUGAAUUCUUUUGCUUUCGAUACUUUUGAGUGCAUUAAAAAAAACUAAUGAAAAGGAAUUAUUUAAGUGGAAUAUUUUAUCUUGGAGAAAUAAUUUCGUUGUCAUAGUGUUUAUUUUUAAUAAAAGGAACCUCUGCCUUAUCUAGUAUAAUAUGUAAAGUAUUAAUAGAAGAAAAGCUUUAACUGUUCUCUAUAAAUCAGCUUAUCAAGUGUAAUAUGAAAAGUAGCAGUUAAAAUCUCGAGUGAAUUAAAAUAUUUUUAGACUUCAGGAAGUUUUAAAUUUAAAACUAAGGUCAUGGCUCAGCAGCAAUUGAAUCUACUAUUAGAAAGCUCUUAGUGAAAAAACUCUUUUUCACCUUUUUGGUAACUGGUAUUAACCUUUUAAAAACCUGCAUUCUAGGCAUUUGAUUUUAUUAUGACUGUCGUCAAGGAAGAUUAAGACUUAAGGCAACUAAAAAAUUAUAUAAUGAAAAAAUGAUUCCUUGUCAUAAAUACAGGUGAUAUAACUAUCAUAUAAAGUGAUGUUGACUAACCAGAACUAGUAAUAUGUUCUAAUAUAUCAUCCUUGGAUCCUUGGGAGCCCAUACUUCUACAGUAAUCAACAUUUAUUGAGUUUAUGAGAGUGUGUGUUUAAAGACAGGGAGAGAGAGAAAACAUGUUUAUUAAAAUGAAACAUGACAAACUAAUGGGUCGGAUUGUGUUCUUUAUGUUCCCUAAAAUUUUUCUUCAUCAUAUUGAAUGUGAUUGAUCUCUAAUUUGGGUAGUGACAUUCCUUGUUAUAUGUUUUAUGUGAUGUUUUGGAUUUACAUUUGUAAAUUUUGGGAAACAGGAUAGUAAGAAGAGUAGCAUAAUUAAAAGACAGGUGGUUGUGCUUUGAAAUGGGCUAUUCUUUAAGAAUGGUAUGAUCUUUAUAGUGGCUUUUGUAAUUUCUUCCUUUUCAAAAUUAUAAACAUUUAUUGUAAUAAAGAAUUUGAUGGAUUAUAGUGAAUUUACUUUUUUUCCAGAAAAUUUCCCUCUUGAGGACAGAAUUUUUUGUUAAGGGUCAAAAAUGACAGUUUGAGUCCAUAAAAGAUUGAAAUCUUUGAAGUGUGUUUUCUAGAACAGGAGUAAGCAAACUUACCUAUUUUUACAUGGCUAAAAACAUCAAAAAAGAAUAAUUCUUUCAGGUGAUGGGUGCACCAAAAUCUCAGAAAUCACCGCUAAAGAACUUAUUCAUGUAACCAAUCACUACCUGUUCCCCCAAAACCUGUUGAAAUAAAAAAUAAAUAAUUCUUUGUGACAUGUGAAAUUUGAAUUUCAUUUUCUAUUUAUAAAUAAAGUCUUAUUGGAACACAGCUGCUUUUGCUUUAUAAUGGCAGAGCUGAGGAGUUUUGACAGAAACUGUAUAUGGCAUUCUCAUUACUUCAAGCUACUGUUUGGUGUACCACAAAUUUCAGUGCUGCCAUUAUUGCUUGACGGUGUUUUGAGUGCCACAUCUGUGACCAGAUUGCAAUUUUUUAUUUUAUUUGUUUAUUUAUUACCACUGUGUAUCCAUCAUGUCAAAAAAAGGAAAGAAGAGAAAAAUAUAGACGUGCUUUUAAGGCACAUUGGAGUGUGGGUUAUUUUGUUAUUGAAUUUAAUAGCAAAACAUUGCUCUUAUUAUGAAGUGACACUAGAGCUGCAAUAGAGGAAUACAGUAUACAUGAAAGUAACUAGACUAAUCAUAUACUACACUAUGUCCAACUCUGAGGAAAGCAAUAGAAAAAUUACAAAACUUAAAAAUGGAAUAUCUCAUCACAGCAUAAUUUCUUCAUAAAAAUGAAAAUGAGGCUGCCACCAAAAUAAGUUUCCAAGUGGCUUAUUUGUUUGCCAAGCAAGGAAAGCCAUUUACUGAUGUUGAGUUAAUUAAAUUGUAUUUUAUUGAAGCAGUCAAAAAAAUUAUGUCCAGAGAAAAUAAACUUGUUUUAGGCUAUUAGCUUUUUGGCAAGCACAGUUGAUUUAAGAGUUGAGGACAUUUGAAGCAACAUCACUAGUCAAUUAAAAAACAAGGCAAAUGAUUUGGAGUGGUUUUUCUCGGCUCUUGAUGAGCCGGCAGAUGUUAUUGAUACAAUUCAGUUGUUCUUUAUUCAAGGAGUCAAUUCCAAGUUUGAAGUGGCAGAAAAGUUGGCCUCUGAAUAGCCUGUGCAGAACAACUACAGGCAAGAAUAUUUUCAAAGCUGAGAAAACACUAAGUACAAUCUGAAGUGGAAUCUGUAAGGAUGUGCUGCAAGCGGUGGUGAUAGAAUACAUACGGAGCAGCAAAAGGCUUAGUUGGAGUAAUUUACAAAGCUUGUAAAACUGAGGAGUUCAUAGUUUAUGGUUAUUCAUUGUUAUUCAUUGGCAGAUACUUUGCAGAAAAUAUUUCCAUCUAUCCAUGUGUGUUACUGAAUCAGUACUGUCAACUGUGAAGUCAGUUUGCUCUUUUGGACUUAACUAGCAUCAGCUGCAUUAAUUUUUGUUAGAAACAGGACAAAUAUCCUGACUGGCUUAGAAGUGGUAAAGUAUAUUUUCACAAUUGUUUGAGCUAAAGGCUGAGAUUGAAAUUUUUUUAAUAAAGAGAACUGCCCUCAACUGCUAUUAAAUACUAAUUAGCUUUGGAAAUUAGCUUUUUGUGAAGAUUGAGUAAUGUUUUUAAAAUGAAUUUAACCUAAGAUUUCAAGGCAAAAUAGUGUCUAUAUUUGAAAGAAUGUGGUAAAGUCAUUUCAGUGGCAACUGAUAUUCAAAUCCCAAAUAAUUUCAGGCUGCUUUAUAUAUUUCUCAAGCUGUCAAAGAAGUUAGAUUGUCAUUCCCACAUAAAUAUGAGUGGACGUAUUUUCUAGUCUCAAACUAUAGUUCCCACAGCAUUUUUCAGAAGUUGACACAAAUGCACAGAAAGUUCCAUAUUUCAAAAAUUUGUUUAAUUUUGUAGUGGAGAAACUUUCUACCUAACCUUGAAUUGGAAGUAAUUAAUCUGCACUGUGAUGACAUACUGAAAGGCAAAUAUCAAAUGAAGAACCAAUGGAUAACUGCCUUCCCAGUAAUGAAUAUGCUCAAUUAAAAUCAUGCUUGUGGGUUAAUAUCAAUAUUUGGCAAUAUCUGUUUCUGUUAAAAGACAUUUUCAAAGACAAAUACAUACAGUCUCAUUACAGAUCAGUGUUUUUUUGUUUGUUUGUUUUUAAGCAAAAGUGCUCUCAUUCUGCGCCCAGGCUGGAGUACAGUGGCACAAUCAUGACUCACUGCAAGCCUGUAUCUCCUGGCCCCAAGCGCUUCUCCUACCUCAGCCUCCUGAGUAGCUGCGACCAUAGGUGCAUACCACCACACCUUAGGUUUUAUUUUUUUAAUUUUUGUAGAGACAGGGUCUCCCUAUGUUGCCCAGGCUGGUCUCGGACUCUUGGGCUCAAACAAUCCACCUGUCUUGGCCUCCCAAAGUGUUGUGAUUACAGACGUGAGCCACUGCGUUUAGCCUGCAGAUCAGUAUUAACAGAUGAGGCCAGGCGUGGUGGCUCAUGCCUGUAAUCCCAGCACUUUAGGAGGCACAGGUGGGCUGAUCACUUGAGAUUAGGAGUUCAAAAACAGCUUGGCCAACAUGGUGAAACCCUGUUUCUACUAAAAAAAAAAUUACAAAAAUUAGCCAGGCAUGGUGGCAUGUGCCUGUAAUCCCGGCUACUUGGGAGGCUGAGGUGGGAGAAUCUCUUGAACCUGGGCGGUGGAGGUUGUAGUGAGCCGAGAUUGUGCCACUGCACUUCAGGCUGGGCAACAGAGCAAGACUCCGUCUCAAAACAAAAUUUAACAGAUGAGUAUUUGUAGUAGAUUUUGAUGAUAGGAAACCCCAAUUAAGUGAGGUGCUAUCUUCUCAAAAAGAAUUUCAUUCUUUUCAUUAGCAAACUUUUAUUAAAAAAAGAAGUGUGUGUGUGUGUGUGUGUGUGUGUGUGUAUUUAUUUAUUUAUUUUUUCAUAUAGGGUCUUCUCUUGUCACCCAGGCUGGAGUGAAGUGGUGUGAUCUCGGCUCACUGCAACCUCUACCUCCUGGGUUCAAGUGAUUCUUGUGCCUCAGCCUCCUAAGUAGCUGGGAUUACAGGCAUCCGCCACCACACCUGGCUAAUUUUUGUGUUUUUAGUAGAGAUGGGGUUUCACCAUGUUGGCCAGGCUGGUCUUGAACUCCUGACCUUAAGUGAUCCGCCCUCCUCAGUCUCCCAACGUGCUGGGAUUAUAGAUGUGAGCCACUGCACCUGGCCUAUUAUAAAAUAUUAUACUCAUUAUUGUAUCUUGGAUUUUGUCAAUAAAAAGUUUUUGGAAAUUGUUUCUGUAUCCAGCCUGGGCGACAGAGUGUCUCCAAAAAAAAAAAAAAAUUGUUUCUGUCUUGUUAUGUAAGUAUCUAUAUGAUUUUGCCUGUUGGCCAGCAAAGACUAAAAUAUUUGUGACUGGGCCCUUUACAGAAAAAGUUACAGAUCUGUGUUCUACAGAAGUACUUCUGAAACAUGAAUGUAUAUAGUAAUUACUGGGGAUCUUGUUAAGAUGCAGAUUCUGGUGUGGUCGGUUUGUGGAGGAACCCAUGAUUUUGCAUUUCUUAUAAGCAUCUUGGUGAUACAGUUGCUGCUGGGCUCAUGCACUGUAGUUUAAGUAGCAAGGCUCUACUGUUUAGGAUUAACAUUUGCUAAGCACCUAUUAUGUGCCAGGAAUUACACCAGGGGCUCUUGAGUAUAUUGCCUCUUUAAAAUAUCUUAUUAGGGCCGGGUGCGGUGGCUCACGCCUGUAAUCCCAGCACUUUGGGAGGCUGAGGUGUGUA